ACAGUCGCCGCGCUUUGCGCACCCUUUUCCUGGCAGGGCUGCGUCCCUGUUCUUCCCAGGAGGCUCCUCGCUGCCUGGUGCCGUAGAGGCCCAUGGAGGAAAAGGAAGAUAAGCAUCAGACUCUGCUACAGCAAACAGGCCUUUCUGCUAUCAUCUGCAGUGAUAAAGACCAGCAUCAGCAGCACCUGGUUGUUAGGAAUGCAAAUUUUGGGGACUUCCCACCCCCGAGACACACAGAAUCAGAAACUCUAUGGCUGGGGCUCAAUAAUCUGGCUUCAACCAAGGCAUCCAGACAGCAUAAAAUAGAGGAUGCUGCUAUAACAUAUGUAAGUGAAAAUGAAGAAAUUAAACACGAAGAAAAACCUGGAAAAAGCAUACAUCAUUCAAAAUCACAUGUUGGAAGAGGACGUAUAUAUUAUGCUAAAUUCAUUAACACAAAUGCAAGAACAUACAAUGAACCAUUUCCCUACAUAGAUCCCAAAAAAGGGCCAGAAAUACAGGGUGACUGGUGGUCACAUGGUAAAGCACUGGAACCUGUCUUCCUACCACCUUACGACUCUAAGAGCACCCAGAGGAGUGACUUCCAAAAACCAUCGUGUCCACUGGUUUUGCCAGUCAAACACAGCAAGAUGCAAAAGCCUUCUUGUGGAAUAGUACCACUUGCCUCUCCUGGUACAUCAGCAGAACUUCAAAACAAUUUUAUAGAAUACAUCUCUUUUAUACAUCAAUAUGAUGCCAGAAAAACUCCGAAUGAGCCUCUCCAGGGAAAGAGACACGGAGCUUUUGUACAGAGAGAGAUAAAACCAGGCAGUAGGCCAACAGUUCCUAAAGGAGCAGAGGUAUUACUGAACACUCCAGGGUCACGUUCAUCAGAACAGUCCAAAAAAACAGAGAAAGGAAACUCAGCGGAAAGCAGAAUGAUCUCACCAGGUCUCUGCCAACAAAAUUCUCAGGAGCUGUUAGAGCCUAAAACUCACUUAUCAGAAACAGACGUCAGACAGGCAGCCAAGGCAUGCCCCAGCACUCCUGAGAGCAGAGAAAAGACCUCAGGCGCCACUCAAACAACUGUAGGAGAUGCUCUUUUCACUAGGCACAAGCCUUUAAAUCCACCAAUUAAAAAAUCAGAAUAAAUUACCUUCUUCAGAUAAAAAUCUAAUCCCUGGAAUAUAGGGAAAUUUCACAAUCAUCAUCUUGGCCCUCACAUUUACUUUUCUGUUAUCAGUAACUUCAGAACAUACAAUUUAUGUAAAUGGAAAAAGAGAAAAAAGACAAUUAAAAUACAACCAAAUGUUAUUAAUAAGAGUGGUCUCCAAUAAGUGGAGUGAGACAUUAUUUCUAUGUCACAUUCUUUAUGAACACAACUUUGUUUUGCACAACACAUGAUCGUAAUUAACAAAUAUAAUACUUUUAGAAGAGAGGCCCUGUUAGACAUGAGUGGACAGCUUUGGAAUCAAACAAACUAGAGUUGGAAUGUUGGCUUCACUUCAUUCCUUGAGCUGUGUGACCUUGGAUGAAACCUUGAGAAAAGGAGCCAAGACUGUAACAGUGGUCCUGUGCCACAGUGCAGGAAGAAAAGGAACAGAGAGAUCACGGGCAUGUUUUUUUAGGUGGUUUCAUGCCAUCUUAUUUUCUCCUUGAAAUACAUUCACAAUGAGGUGACUGGCUCUGUGGGAAGCCUAUGGCCAUGUUGUAAUGACACUCAAUCAGCCCAGUGGAGAGGGCCACAUGGCAAGGAACUAAGGCCUCCCACCAACAGCCAGCAAAGAACUGAGACCUUCUGCCUACAGUCAUGAGUCCUCUUGGAAGAGAAUCUUCCCAUCUCAUUCAAGCCUUCAGAUGACCAUGGCAUGGGCAAACUUUGAUUGCAGUCUCAUGACAGACCCAGAGCCAGAACCAUCCAGUUAAGCUGCUGUUGAAUUCCUGAUCCCAUCUAAAUCAUGUUAAUACCUGUCAUAAACAGAUAACUAACAGAUUAAUAAGCAGCUUAUAUACAGGCUUAGCUACAAAUCAUUCCAUAUAAUGUUUUACACAAACUGUUUUUUCCUAGUUUUGUGUUGAAGUGAAUGAAGCUCUAGAAAGCCAAAGGACAGAAGGAGCCAGGACCUCUGAGUCAUUUGGAGGAGUGCUACCCUAGAAAGCCACCCCUAUCAUGUUAAACCACAAAUUUGGGACUUGUUUGCUAUAGUAGAUAGUGCUAAUUCUAUGUAAUAUACUCUCGUUUUUACUUCUCAUAGCAUUUAUUGUUCUCUACCAUAAAUAAUUAUUCGCGUAAAUAUAUUUUUUCAUUUUAGUCUAUUAGUUGCUUUAAAAAAAAAAAAACUACAUUGCCAUGGUUUGACUGUGUCCUCCAAAAGCAUGUGUUGGAAACUUAAUUGCCAUUGUAACAGUAUUAAGAGGUGGGACCUUUCAGAGGUGAGUAGGACAUGAGGGCUCUGCCUGCAUGAAUGGAUUAAUGCUGUUAUUUCAGGAGCGAUUUUCUUAUAAAAGGACAAGGUAGGCCCCCUUCACACUCUCUCUGUUGCACACUCUCUUGGCUGUCUGCCUUCUGACAUGGGAUGACACAGCAAGAAGGCCCUCCCCAGGUGCAACCCCUCCAUCUUGGACUUCUCAGCUUCUAGAACUAUGAGCCAAAUACAUUUCAUUUCUUUAUAAAUUACCCAGUCUUUGGUAUUCUGUUAUAGCAGCACAAACCGGACUAAGACAAACAUGAAAUGAGAAAUUACAAGACGCCUGGUGGUAUGUGCUUUGCCAAUGUAUCUCAAUUAAUUCUCGCAAUAAACCUCUCAAGUAAAUACUA